UGUUUUUGGCGUGCUAAUUUGUUUUAACUUUGUGAACAUAAUUAUAGAAAAAAUUUUAGCGUUUUCCAUUGAUGAUAAGUACUGUGAUUAAAUAUGUGGUUUUAUACAUUAAGAGCAUGCCGCAUAGAGAGCUGUCUCUUUUUAAAUUUUUAGUAUAUUGAAAUCGUUAUAUUUUCCAAGAUUUAUUGCCUGGAACUCACCAGAUCAAGUUUUACUAACUAGUGGUAAUUUAAAAUAAUCUAUAAGUACAUUAGUAUCAGAGGCAUGCAAUUAUUUUUGCUAAACUACCAUGGCUAAACAUAUCAAACUAGAUGAUUUCCAGACUUAAAAGUAUGUUUAGCCUCUUACCAAUAGAGGCGUUUCAGCUAUUUAUUUCUGGAAGAUUAUUUGUAUAAAUCUGCCUGAUUGACUUGUGAAGUAAAUCUUUGCAAGUUUCUAGACCCUACAAAUUUGGGAAGCCAACAUCUCCCAGGCUAAAAGAGAAAGUUUCCAGCUUUACAGAGACCUGAAUGCCAUUUGGUCAUUCACUUAUUCAUGCACUUCUUAAAUAUGUAUUAAACACUCACCAUGCAUUGCUGUAGCUACAGGGGCUAUAAAGGUAGAUAGGAAAUGGGUCCUGCCCUUAAGGAGCAUAUGUCCUUGCAGGGGAAAUUGAGAUACAGUUUGUAAGUGCUGUAAAGAGGCAGACGCACAGUACAGUGUUGACACAAAGGUGGACUAAUCCACAAGCCAUGUUUCUUGGUCCAGUGUCUCCUCUCUGGCUUCUGUGAUCAUCUUGUUUAUCCUCCCUCUUGGUUGUAUGAGUUGGGCAAGGAGAGGUGUUAGGAGAAAAAAAAUCAGCUUUAAUGGACCUAGAGAAUUAGGACCAAGGUAGGCUCAGGGCAAAUGUUCCCUUUGAGCCUGUUCACCAUCCCUAUAAAGUGCUGGGCACAUUCUAGAAUCUUGGCAACUGAGUUGAAGCCAAGGUUCUCCGAGCUCUGACUUAAUGUGGGAAGAGAGUCACUUCUUCCCUUGAAAUCUACCUUAGCAGUGAUGUUUCUUCUCGUUGAUACAUUCACUCCUGCCUUUUAAAUGCUUUCUGAUGCAGCACCUGGGAAACUGAGAAUUGUUCAUGGAGAUGUCUUGACAUUUAAGGUAGAAAAGGCUUUUUCAGAAAGUCUUAAAAGACCCUGGGAAGAUGAUCCUCCAAAUGUACAUAUUAUUGGAAAUCUGCCUUUUAGUGUUUCAACUCCACUGAUUAUCAAGUGGCUUGAAAAUAUUUCCUGUAGAGAUGGACCUUUUGUUUAUGGCAGAACUCAGAUGACUUUGACUUUUCAAAAGGAAGUGGCAGAGAGACUUGCAGCCAAUACAGGAAGCAAACAGCGUAGUCGCCUCUCUGUUAUGGCUCAGUACCUCUGCAAUGUUCGACACAUCUUUACGAUUCCAGGACAAGCUUUUGUCCCCAAACCAGAGGUGGACGUGGGCGUGGUGCACUUCACUCCCUUGAUACAGCCCAAGAUAGAGCAGCCAUUCAAGCUGGUGGAAAAAGUGGUUCAGAAUGUAUUUCAGUUCCGAAGGAAAUACUGCCAUCGAGGGCUCAGAAUGUUAUUCCCUGAAGCGCAGCGCUUGGAAAGCACGGGCAGGCUGUUAGAGUUGGCAGACAUAGACCCUACUCUUCGGCCCCGCCAGCUCUCCAUCUCACACUUUAAGAGCCUCUGUGAUGUAUACAGAAAAAUGUGUGAUGAAGACCCACAACUCUUUGCAUAUAAUUUCAGAGAAGAACUCAAGCGAAGAAAAAGCAAAAAUGAAGAAAAAGAAGAGGAUGACGCAGAGAAUUACAGACUCUAGCUGCUGCCUGGGGGCGAGCAGCCUACCAGAUGUCGAUUUGCACUACGUGGAGCUUCUUAUAUAGGUACUCUUUUGUCUUUACAGAAUGACGAUACAAAUGCCAAUGACCAGAUGUGACUUAUUUUCCUUUUACUAUACAGCUUGGCAGAGAAAAUAAAUAUCAUCAAAUAAGAUACAGUACAAGCUUUCUUUUAAUAUAUACUGUAUAGAUAGUUAUGACAUGUUUAGUAUAAACAGCAUCUAUUACAAUCUAUCUUACAAAAAUGAAGUAUCUGCACAUUUUGCCCCUAAACCACAUUAAAAUAACUUAAAUAUGCUUUAAAUAAAGCAAAAACUAACAAACAGCUGAAAGAAAAUGCCCAGAGGAUUUUAAAAAAUGGCCCUUUGAAAACUAUUAAUCACGACUUCCCCAGCCUUACUUUUUCCACAUAACUUAAUUAUUAGAAUGUAAUUUUAAGGAUCCUAAAUCAUUUGAUACCUGCUCAAAGUGGAUAUAAACUAAGUAAUUUACAGAUUCUGACCAGUUUCAUCUAGGUUUCUGAUCCACAAUAAAUUAAAAUAACUUAAAUCUUUACAACCAUUUUGUGGGAAAAUGUAUACUGCACAAAACCCAGGAAUGAACAGUUUUUUUUUUUUUUUUUUUUUGCAAUUUCCACUUUACCACCAGUUUAAAAGUAAAAUGAGGAAUUUAACCCAUAUCUGGAUUGAAUCAUACUAUGAUUUUCCGUGGCUCUCUGUUUCAUAAAAACACUCCUCACUGACAACAGAUGUUAAACUCUGGACACUGAAUUCUCGCUCUAGAACAGAAUUUAGGUCGAUGGUGGCAUUUUCAGACUGACUGUCAAGGGACUGGUGACGGAUCUGCGCCUUGAGCAAAGUUCCUCUGUCCCUCUUGGUGCUGUUGGCUUUUCGUUUAAUGGGGCAGAAGUGCCCCCGGACCAGUUUGGGCUGCUCUCCUCCUUUCUGACCCUCACCCGACUCCGGGCCAGGCUGCUGCUCAGCCUCGGGGUGAACGUCUGGGUCCUCGGAAAUCCUCAGUCUCUGGAACUGAAUUUCGAUGUCUUUAGUAGGGCUGCCCUGCUUCACAGUCUGACGGUGGUCAUCAUCUUCAUCGCUCAGGAUGUCACUCUCUUUGAUGAGAUUGUCGGCAAAAUCUGCCAAGCCGGGGUGUGGGUAUUUCCCGGGAGAAGUGCUCUUGGAGUCCUGCCUGCCCUCAGCCGUGGGGCAGCCGCUGCUCUGGGUGCCGCUGCUCAAGCUGCCCUCGUCAGAGUCCAGCAAGGUUCCCUUGCCAGUCUCACCGGUCCACUCGUUGCUGGAGGAAUUCUUCAGGACUUUUAAAGACCUGGAUGAAGCUACAGUGAGAAAAACACAUUUCGCUGUGAUACAGAAACAGGUUACACAAUGUGUAAUGUUUGCCUCAAAGCUUGUGUAAGAUUUAACAUUAAGAUUUUAUUUUAUGAUAUGACUUCAGUUAGCAACUAUCCUGGUAAUUAGGCAAAAAUGUAGCUACUGAAAACAUGGACAUUUUUGACUUAGGUUUACAGUUGUAAGUUAGGCAAUUCAGCAUUUUUAGAUUACCAGAGCUCAAUUAUGUAAAUAGAACUAGACACUAGAAACUACUACAUGGGCUAAGAUUCUUAUUUUGCCAAGGAGUAAGUUGAAAAGUUAAUUGGUAAUAAUAAAUCUAGGCUCCUUUCUUUCA